AGUCCUUCAGCGGCCGGGUUCGCGCCGCGGUCGCCGGCUGCUUACGUGGGCGGGCCUAGUGUGGGGCUGAGGGUGCGGGUCGCUAUGGCGGUGGACAUCACGCUGCUAUUCCGGGCCAGCGUCAAGACCGUGAAGACGCGGAACAAGGCGCUGGGAGUGGCGGUGGGCGGCGGGGUCGAUGGCAGCCGGGACGAGCUGUUCCGCCGGAGCCCCCGGCCCAAGGGCGACUUCUCCAGCCGGGCCCGCGAAGUGAUUUCUCACAUUGGCAAACUGAGAGAUUUUCUUCUGGAACACAGGAAAGAUUAUAUUAAUGCUUAUAGCCAUACCAUGUCUGAAUAUGGGAGGAUGACAGACACAGAACGAGACCAGAUAGACCAGGAUGCCCAGAUAUUCAUGAGGACCUGUUCAGAAGCAAUUCAGCAACUACGAACAGAAGCUCACAAGGAGAUACAUUCCCAGCAAGUGAAGGAGCACAGGACCGCUGUUUUGGAUUUCAUUGAAGAUUACUUGAAAAGAGUAUGUAAACUUUACUCAGAACAGAGAGCCAUCCGAGUUAAAAGAGUGGUGGAUAAGAAAAGAUUAUCUAAGCUGGAACCAGAACCAAAUACAAAGACAAGAGAAUCCACAUCUUCUGAGAAAGUUUCACAGAGUCCUUCAAAAGACUCUGAAGAAAACCCUGCCACUGAAGAACGUCCAGAAAAAAUUUUGGCUGAAACACAACCUGAAUUGGGAACGUGGGGAGAUGGCAAAGGCGAAGAUGAGUUAUCCCCAGAAGAAAUACAAAUGUUUGAACAGGAAAAUCAGCGACUAAUUGGUGAAAUGAACAGCUUGUUUGAUGAAGUGAGGCAAAUCGAAGGGAGAGUGGUUGAGAUUUCCAGACUCCAAGAGAUAUUCACGGAAAAGGUUUUGCAACAGGAAGCUGAGAUUGACAGCAUUCACCAGUUAGUUGUGGGGGCAACUGAAAAUAUCAAGGAAGGCAACGAAGACAUAAGAGAGGCCAUUAAAAACAACGCUGGCUUCCGCGUGUGGAUCCUCUUCUUCCUCGUGAUGUGCUCCUUCUCCUUGCUCUUCCUCGACUGGUACGACAGCUAGCCAGGGCCACGGGGGCCCAGCACGAGAGUCCUCAUGGGCACUCACAGACUGCGUGCUUUCAUGUACUUCCAGUGCUGGAGCAUGGUAUGACCAGAUUUUAUCACAGUGCCAUUUGAAGGGAAAGGAGUUCAGACAGACAGACGUAUUCCCCAAAAAGGGAUACCCCAGGCCGAUGGUGUUCAGCCAUUUAGCAGCUGAAAAAGGAAACAGUGCACACCAAUGGGAGGCAGCCUGCGUAGCCCUCAUCAGGCAAGACAGACUGAAUGCAGGAGUGGGUGAUUAGCUGCUCCUUGAACUUGAGGCUGCCUUGGCAGCAGGGGCACAGCAGGCCUCAAGAGCCCCUAAUUGUCUCAGGGUUCAAAGGAAGACACUGACCUUUCCCAUCCCGGUAGCUUCAGGGAAGAUCAUAGUUAAUAACGUCUCUCAACAAAUGAUUACUUCUUUGUUUCCUUGUGGCUUCUUGUCUGUCUGAGUCAACGAAUACACAGACUUACUGGAUUAUAGAAGAGAAAAUUCACAUCUGCCUUGUUAAUCUAAUAAAUAUAAUUACAGCCCCUUAAUGUGUUGUCAAUGAGUCUAAGUUGACAAAUUCAGUGGCAGCCCAGCCACCUCCUAUCAAUCAAUCAGGGAAGAAAUGCAGGGGAGACUGGGGCCCUCAGUGAGGGGCUGCCUGGCAUUACUCCUCCAAAGACUGCUGCCCCCAGAACAGGCAGGGGGUGUGGGAGGGCCAGUUUCCCGCCACUGGGUCCAAGGAGCCUUUGUUCAAAGGAAGAAGUGGGCCACGGAAGAACGGGCCUGCUUCUCUCGUGCCUGUGCUUCUGACCUCCAGGAACUGUAAACAGGAACACCUAUGUGUAACUGAAGGCAUGAGACAUCUGUACAGGAAGCAUCCCAGCGCCCACAUGGGCAUGAGACAGUCUGCACUGCGCCUGGUGAAAUGCGUGUGUGUACAGACAGUCCACUGGGCAGCACAGGUAUCCUCAUGUUCUUUAUUUGCACAGAGUGAAAUGUCAGAAGUUACAUGUAAAUGAAUUCACAGUCAAUAAAGUCCACGUCUACCUGGAAA